AAGCUGGCCCUGAAAUGGCACCCGGGUAAGUACCUGUCCCGCAGCCCCCGCGGCCACUCGGAGAAGCCCGGCCCUCCCCGACCUUCCCUUCCCCCGGGCGGACUCCGCGGAGCCAGCAGAGAGGGACCUGGCGGCCUAGGAGCUCCUUGCCCCGCCCGGCCAGUGCCCGGAGCCGCCCUGCCCGUCUCGGUGGGCGAAGCGCUCUGCCCUGGCGCACCCCGGCUCACACCCCAUCUCCUCAUACCCGCGACCCCGGCCCCGCAUCGCCACUGUAGGGGGAAAACUGCAGUCCAACAACCUCACUUGCUCCCGCUACCGGGUCGCAGACACCACGAGGGAGCAGUCGGGAACUCGGAACUCAGACCUGCCCCAGGCUUGCUUUUCCCUGCGUCCCUUGCAGCGCAGCCUCUCGGUGUUUUUCCUCCGCUGCCCUCCACCUCGUCCGGGAAUCCCAGAUACUUCAACCUGAUAUAAAAAUCUGGAUAAUGCCGCAGAAGCAGCUGAACAAUUUAAAUUAAUCCAAGCAGCAUAUGAUGUGUUGAGUGACCCUCAGGAAAGAGCAUGGUAUGAUAAUCAUAGAGAGGCCCUACUUAAAGGUGGGUUUGAUGGCGAAUAUCAAGAUGACAGCUUAGAUUUGCUACGCUAUUUCACCGUUACCUGUUAUUCUGGUUAUGGAGAUGAUGAAAAGGGAUUUUACACGGUGUAUCGUAAUGUUUUUGAAAUGAUUGCCAAGGAAGAACUAGAAUCUGUGUUAGAGGAAGAGGUUGAUGAUUUCCCAACUUUUGGAGACUCCCAGAGUGACUAUGAUACGGUAGUCCAUCCUUUCUACGCUUAUUGGCAGAGUUUCUGCACUCAAAAGAAUUUUGCAUGGAAGGAAGAAUAUGAUACACGACAGGCUUCAAACCGCUGGGAAAAACGAGCCAUGGAAAAAGAAAACAAAAAGAUUCGGGACAAAGCAAGGAAAGAGAAGAAUGAGCUUGUCCGUCAGCUGGUAGCUUUCAUUCGUAAAAGAGAUAAAAGAGUGCAGGCGCAUCGAAAACUUGUGGAAGAACAGAAUGCAGAGAAGGCGAGGAAAGCCGAAGAGAUGAGGCGGCAGCAGAAGCUAAAGCAGGCCAAACUGGUGGAGCAGUACAGAGAACAGAGCUGGAUGACUAUGGCCAAUUUGGAGAAAGAGCUCCAGGAGAUGGAGGCACGGUACGAGAAGGAGUUUGGAGAUGGAUCGGAUGAAAAUGAAAUGGAAGAACAUGAACUCAAAGAUGAGGAGGAUGGUAAAGACAGUGAUGAGGCCGAGGACGCUGAGCUCUAUGAUGACCUUUACUGCCCAGCAUGUGACAAAUCGUUCAAGACAGAAAAGGCCAUGAAGAAUCACGAGAAGUCAAAGAAGCAUCGGGAAAUGGUGGCCUUGCUAAAACAACAGCUGGAGGAGGAAGAAGAAAAUUUUUCAAGACCUCAAAUUGAUGAAAAUCCAUUAGAUGACAAUUCUGAGGAAGAAAUGGAAGAUGCACCAAAACAAAAAGUCAAGUAUUUGACAUUUCGAUUUAUAUUUGCUCUUAGGCUUUCUAAAAAACAGAAGAAAAAGAAACAGAAACCAGCACAGGAUGUACCUGGCAAAGAUUCAUAUCUGCCUGCAGCUCACUUUCAGAUGGCUUGGGGAAAAAAGUGUGUGUUGGGAGAGAGAAGAGAUGGAGAGAGCGAGCACAAAUGUGCCAAAAUGUUGCUUGAAAACAGACAGAAUUAUGAUGACAAUUUCAAUGUAAAUGGACCUGGAGAAGGAGUAAAGGUUGAUCCAGAAGAUACUAACUUAAAUCAAGACAGUGCCAAAGAAUUGGAAGAUAGUCCCCAGGAAAAUGUCAGUGUCACAGAGAUCAUUAAACCAUGUGAUGAUCCAAAAAGUGAAGCUAAAAGUGUUCCUAAACCCAAAGGAAAGAAAACCAAAGAUAUGAAAAAACCUGUCAGAGUACCUGCUGAACCACAAACAAUGAGUGUUCUUAUCAGCUGUACAACCUGCCAUAGUGAAUUUCCAUCUCGGAAUAAACUUUUUGACCAUCUAAAGGCCACAGGUCAUGCAAGAGCACCUUCAUCAUCGUCUUUAAACAGCGCAACAAGUAGUCAAAGCAAGAAAGAGAAACGUAAAAACAGAUAGAGAUUCUGCCUGUGCUUUUGUUUGACUGUCUCUAGAUUUUGAAACCAAAAAACUGAACUGAAAUCAUCUAAAGAGUUAAAAUUUCAGUGAUCUGCAAUUAAUUACAUUGUGGAAGAUUAUUUUUUAUCUUGUAAAAACACUUUUUUGGUUUAAUAUAUAUUUUUAAAACAUUUCACUAGUGAUUGAAUUCUACUUUUGCCAUCUGAAUUGACUUGAAUGUCUUAAAACAGGUAAAUACUGUAAAGUGUGUAUUCUUGAUGUUUAUUGGCUCAUGUGGACAGAAAUGUACAGGGAGAAUUACAUUAUUUUAACACACAGAAGUGCAACUUUCUGCUUUAUUUUCUGAAUUUCACAUUACUUUUACUUAAUGCUUUUGUGUUUUGUUAAUACUUCAUAAUAUGUGAAAAACUCGGAUCUUUUAAAAAGCAUCAUAGAUCAUUUUUCCAUAUGACACUGGUUCCGAUUUUAAAAAUUAUUUUUAAAUAACCGAUUAUUGAUUACUGUAUUUUUUUUCUCAAGAACAGUGAUAGGUAGAAACUAAUUGAACAUUUGGUAGUCUUUCAAGAAUAGUGUCUCUUCAAGGUUUUACUUGAUUUAAUUUGAUAUUUUACUGGUUUACCAGUAAGGUGUAUUGUUCAGUUUUUUGCUCCGAUUUGAAUUGUGGAGGUGGAAGCAAAUUAGUUUACAUGGCAUGUCCUCCCUAGGCACAGUGACAGCUGUAAAGUAUGACGGAACAAGGUAGCAGAUGGUACAGAAUUUAUACUAUUUAAGAAGAGAUGUGGUGUUCUUCAUUGAGUUUUUUUCUUCACUAUUUUCAGAAGUUUUUGUUCUUUUUUUUUUUUCCAUCACUCAGUGGAGAAAAGCUUUGUUAAUGAAAGAUUUUGUGAUAGAGCUGAUGCUUAUACAUCUAUUCUAUAACAGUGAUGAAUAUUAACACAAAGGAAAUAUGGAGAACUGUUAUAACUGAGUGUUAGAACAGUCGUGUACAUUGAUCAGUAUUGAGUCCAUUUUUAGGAUGGAUUAGUCAGUUCUUUUCAUUGGUCUUGAAAGUAAUUUUGGCUGGUCGCGGUGGCUCACGCCUGUAAUCCCAGCACUUUGGGAGGCCGAGGCGGGCGGAUCACGAGGUCAGGAGAUCGAGACCAUCCCGGCUAAAACGGUGAAACCCCGUCUCUACUAAAAAUACAAAAAAUUAGCCGGGCGUAGUGGCGGGCGCCUGUAGUCCCAGCUACUUGGGAGGCUGAGGCAGGAGAAUGGCGUGAACCCGGGAGGCGGAGCUUGCAGUGAGCCGAGAUCCCGCCACUGCACUCCAGCCUGGGCGACAGAGCGAGACUCCGUCUCAAAAAAAAAAAAAAAAAAAAAAAGAAAGUAAUUUUAAACUCACUGGCUUGAAAUGUGUGCUUUCUGUACAAUGAAGUUAUUGCUUUCCAUAUAUCCUUGAAUCUUCAGAUUAACGAAAUGAACAAAUUUUCGGUUACAGAUCAGCUCUCAAACACUAAAGUCCUUAAUGGCAAGGUCUUUUCUGAUAGCUUCAUGGAUAGUAUUGAUGAUCAGAUUUCUUCUGUGUUAUUGUCUUAAAAAUAAGCAUUUGAACCUUAAUUUAAAUUCUUUUCUUUUCCAUUUAGAGAUAUGUUUUUUUCUUUACCUUCAUACCUUUCUAUUUCUUGCUAAUUUCUAUCACUAAUUCCUUAUAAUUGUCCCUGCUCCCCUUCUUGAUCUCUUCAGGGGGAAUACUAGGCAGUUUUGUAUCUUCUGAUCUCGUACCCUGAGACUUCAUCUGAAUGUGCUCUGCCGCCUUCUUAUCUGAACUAGAUGAAUUGGCCAUAAUUAUGAAUAGGAAUAUUAAUGAACCAGAGGACAUACUAGUCACAUGUUAUUAUACACUAAAAAAUAGGAAGUCAUCUUGAAAGGCAGUUAAUGUACUGCAAAUGUCCCUAUGACUUCUUUGCUUUCUCUUAUACCAAACAUGCAGGUAUUUAAUUUGUUUAAUGAGGGUUGAGUGGAGUUAUGUGUCGCUUUUAUUCGGAUUGACGAAAAUCAACCAUAAUUUUCAAGGGAUCUUCAUGGGUUGUGACUGGAAGCUGACCUUAGUCUUGCGUCUCAUCCUUUAUGAUGUUGAGAAAUCAUCUAAUUUCUCAGAACUUUUUCUUAUCUCUAACACAGUUAUUACCAUAAUAAUAUUGUCUCCAUUUAUCAUACAGGAUCAUUAUGAAAGUAAAAUGAAGUAGUAUAUAUGAAAAUGCUUUUUAAACACAAAAGCUUUAUACAAAAUAUUGUUGAAUUUAAAUAAGGUAAAUCUUUUUUAGUUUAUAUAUUUGCAGACUAUACAUGUUGGAUUAAAUGGGCAAUUAAGUUUUAUAGGAAUUUGCUUCCUAAGUCUACUUUUGAAGAGGAAAACAGGAACGUACCAUAUAUUUUGCUAAGGGUAAAAUAUUUUUGGUGAAUUGCAGACAUUUAAUUUCACUUGUCUGAGGUAAAACAAUAAACUAAAAUACAUGGGCAUGCAUCUUACACUGAUCUUAUUAGAGGUCAGUGCUAAGUACCCAUCUUGAUUGAAGUUAGCUCAGAUGUGGAGAUUCAUAGAAUGAGGGUCCAGGAGAAGAAAGUUAGGGGAAAUCUCAUUUUCUUUCUGUAAUUCAUUCAGUGGUGCCAAAGCUGGGGGUUCCCUACAAUGGCUAUUUAGACUUUCCCUGCUUCAAAAUAAGAGCAGUAUCCUUAGCUCUAGCCAAGCAUUUUUCUAAUUCCUGCCUUUGGUCACAAAGAAGGAAAAGCAGAGCUGUGAAUGAGUUAGUGGAGGUCAAGUCACAUCAGAGUUCAUGACCUAGUGAUUGCUGGUGAAGUAAUAUUGGAAUUUUGGUACCAUGAGAAGACUUAUAAAGGAUUUCAUCAGAAGUUUUCAUUUUUUCUAAAUCCUCCCCUACAAAAUUUUCAGAUUGGAAAUUACUCUUGUAUUUGUAGAAGAUUGUCUCUAAAAUUGUGGUUUAACUCACGCAGGAAGUAAAAUUCCUAUAGCAAGACAUAGUUUCAUUUUAGAGGACCCCCAAAAUCCCGUGAAUUCUCUGGUGAUGAUUCUAGCCUAACCUUCAACAUAAAAUAAUGAAGAGAACUUUUAAACUUUUUUAUGAAUUCCUAAACAUUACCAUUUAUGUGGCAGAAGUUCUGUUCCCUAUAAUCUGCAAUGCUGAAGUAUCUCUAUUCAAUUCCCUUCCUUAUCUGUUAAAUUUAAUGUCUUUAUACUAAAAAUAUAGGCUCUUGGGAUUGGAGAGGAAAAAUUAGAGGUGAUUUUCAGAUUUCUUGUUCUAUGGAAGAGGAAGCUGAGCUCAGGGAGAUAUGAGCUCCACAGCCACAGCUGGUUAGGGGCGGCUGCCAGUAGAACAGGGCAGAUGCCUGGACUCCCAACUCAGUAGGCCUUCUGUUACACCUCAAAAUGUGUUACAUGGGAAGAAAAAGAUUAAGAAAAAGCAAGAUAAUUUUGAAGAAGGACGAGAGGAAGAGGCAUGAACUUGUCCUAACAAUGUCAAAGAAUAUUUUAAAGGUAUACCAGUUAAAGUAGUGUGUGGCUGGUGCCAGUAGAGGUCAGUCAAGGGAUCCCUGACGAGAAUAAAGAGCCCAGAAACAGGUCCAUGUUUAUAUGGGAACUUGAUUUUUGACAGAUACGGCAAGCUCUAUGGGGAAAACAAUAUGUACUACCUUAUACCCUUCCCCAAAAACAAAGGGAUUAAAGACCUAAAUAUGAAGACAAAACUUUUAAAUGAGAAUCUAUAAGGUUAUUUUCAUGAUUUUGCAAAUGGGAAGGAUUUCUUUAAAGCAAGACACAAAAGCAUACACAGGAAAAAAUGAUGCAUAAAAACAUGGCUUCUGUAGAACAAUAGAGACUGUAAAAGAACAAGCUACAGACAAGGAAAUGUUUGCAAUGCAUGGAACUGUCAAAGGAUUCGUAUCUGGAAUACAUUAAAGAAGCAAAAGAACCUCAUACAAAAGUCAUUGAGUAAAUGACAGCCAUGCAUUAGAACAGCAAUUCUCAAAACUUUUGGUCUCAAGAUCCCUUUACACUCUUCAAAAGUGAGAACCCCAAAGAGUUUUCAUGUAUGUGGGUUAAAUCUAUUGAUAUUUUCUGUUAGAAUUUAAAAAUUAUGUUAAAAAAAUAAGAAGAAUGACUAUUUUUCAAAACAAAAAAUGAGAAGAGUGGUAUUGUUUUACAUUUUUACAAAUCUCUUUAACAUUUAGCUUAAUAAAAGAUAGCUGGCCUCUCA